UUGUGCCUUUGUAGAAAGGAGCUUGCACUGUCAGUUUUCUAUGAAUUAUCUUUUUCCCUGGUCCUUCUCUUUUUCCACGUCCUUCUUCCCUUCUUCCAUGUCCUUCUUCCCUUCUUCUCAUGUCGUUCUAUUCUUCCACGUACUUCUUCCCUGAAGCCUAGAAAGGUUGCAAAAUCUUAACAUCCUCCACAAGUGAGGAAAGGCCCAUGGCUUCAACCCUCAAAAGACUUAAAAUCUGGCUAGAGUUUUAAAAGGAGUGUCCUCAUAUGUAGUCAUUCUUCAAACAUUUGGUGAGGCCACCUCUGUACCAAUCCUGUGCUCACAGAAAAGAUAGCAAGAGGAGAGCCCUGGGCAUUGUCUUCAUAGAGCUCACAGGCUACUGAGCUCACAGAGCUGGAGCCAUAAUAAAGGGAAUCUACAUAUUUUUAGCCAGUACUUCUCAAAGUGGGUGGAAACAGGCUGGGCACAGAGGCUCACACCUGUGAGCGCUUUGGGAGGUUGAGGCAGCACUUUGGGAGGCCAAGACAGGAGGAUCAUUUGAGCCCAGGAGUUUGAGACCAGCCCGAGUGAUGUAGUAAGAACUCAUCUAUCAAAAAAUAAAACCUGUCUCUACAAAAAAUUAAAAAAUUAGCUGGCCGUAGUGGUGCAUGCCUGUAGUCCCAGCUACUCAGGAGGCUGAGGUGGGAGGAUUGCUUUAGCUCAAGAGUUAGAGGCCACAGUGAGCUAUGAUCUCACCACUUCACUGGACAACAGAGUAAGACUCUGUCUCUUUAAAAAAAAAAAAAGCUGGGCAUGGUGGUGUGUGCUUGCAGUCCCAGCUACUGGGGAGGCUGAGGCAGGAGAAUCACUUGAACCAGGGAGGCGGAGGUUGCAGUGAGCUGAGAUAGCGCCACUGCACUUCAGCCUGGUGACAGAUCGAGACUCCAUCUCAAAAAAAAAAAAAAAAAGUGGGUGGAAAUAUAUCAGAAGUCAUCUGGGGAAGUAUUUCUUCUACAAUUGAGAACUGCUUUAUGCAAAAAAAGUCACUUUGGCUGGGUUAGUAGGUGCAUGAACCAGGUCCUGAACCACAACAGGAGCCUCCUAAGGCGAGAGGUUGAAGCUUCUCUUCUGACUCUGGGAUCAGCCCCAGAGCAGGCCCUGCCCCCAGGAGUCUGUGUGUCUGCUCUCUUCUUCCCAUCCAUAUUCCUUUCAGGAGGGUCACGCAGCACAAUGCCAGCUCUGCCCCUGGACCAACUCCAGAUCACCCACAAGGACCCGAAGACAGGAAAGCUGAGGACUUCACCAGCGCUGCACCCCGAGCAGAAGGCAGACCGGUAUUUUGUGUUAUACAAACCGCCCCCUAAAGACAACAUUCCCGCCCUAGUGGAGGAGUACCUGGAACGCGCCACCUUCGUAGCCAAUGACCUCGACUGGCUCCUGGCCUUGCCUCACGAUAAAUUCUGGUGCCAGGUGAUCUUUGACGAGACUCUACAGAAGUGCCUGGACUCCUACCUGCGCUAUGUCCCCCGCAAAUUCGACGAGGGGGUGGCCUCAGCCCCUGAGGUUGUUGACAUGCAGAAGCGCCUCCAUCGAAGUGUUUUUCUCACCUUCCUCCGCAUGUCCACUCACAAGGAAUCCAAAGAUCACUUCAUUUCCCCUUCUGCGUUUGGAGAAAUCCUCUACAAUAACUUCCUCUUUGACAUUCCAAAGAUCCUGGACCUCUGCGUGCUCUUUGGAAAAGGCAACUCACCACUGCUCCAGAAGAUGAUAGGAAACAUCUUUACACAGCAGCCAAGUUACUACAGUGACCUGGAUGAAACCCUGCCUACCAUCCUUCAGGUCUUCAGCAAUAUCCUCCAGCACUGUGGUUUGCAAGGGGACGGGGCCAAUACCACACCCCAGAAGCUUGAGGAGAGGGGCCGAUUGACCCCCAGUGACAUGCCUCUCCUGGAAUUAAAGGACAUUGUUCUCUACCUUUGUGAUACCUGCACCACACUUUGGGCCUUUCUGGAUAUCUUCCCUUUGGCUUGCCAGACCUUCCAGAAGCACGACUUUUGUUACAGACUAGCUUCCUUCUACGAAGCAGCAAUUCCCGAAAUGGAGUCUGCAAUUAAGAAGAGGAGGCUUGAAGAUAGCAAGCUUCUUGGUGACCUGUGGCAGAGGCUCUCCCAUUCCAGGAAGAAGCUAAUGGAGAUUUUCCACAUCAUCCUGAACCAGAUCUGCCUCCUUCCCAUCCUAGAAAGCAGCUGUGACAACAUUCAGGGCUUCAUCGAAGAGUUCCUUCAGAUCUUCAGCUCCUUGCUGCAGGAGAAGAGGUUCCUCCGGGACUAUGAUGCACUCUUCCCCGUGGCCGAAGACAUCAGCUUGCUGCAGCAGGCCUCAUCAGUCUUGGACGAGACGCGGACUGCCUACAUCCUCCAGGCAGUCGAGAGUGCAUGGGAAGGGGUGGACAGACGGAAAGCCACAGAUGCUAAAGACCCAUCGGUGAUUGAGGAGCCUAAUGGGGAGCCUAACGGGGUCACGGUGACAGCAGAGGCAGUCAGUCAAGCAUCAUCACAUCCGGAGAACUCGGAGGAAGAGGAGUGCAUGGGAGCAGCCGCGGCUGUGGGCCCUGCCAUGUGUGGGGUGGAACUGGACUCUCUCAUCUCCCAAGUGAAGGACCUGCUGCCAGACCUUGGUGAGGGCUUCAUCCUGGCCUGCCUGGAGUACUACCACUACGACCCAGAGCAGGUGAUCAACAAUAUCCUGGAGGAGCGGCUGGCCCCCACCCUCAGCCAGCUGGACCGCAACCUAGACAGAGAAAUGAAACCAGACCCUACACCCCUGCUGACGUCUCGCCACAACGUCUUCCAGAAUGACGAGUUUGAUGUGUUCAGCAGGGACUCAGUAGACCUGAGCCGGGUGCACAAGGGCAAGAGCACCAGGAAGGAGGAAAACACGCGGAGUUUGCUGAACGACAAGCGUGCAGUGGCGGCACAGCGGCAGCGCUACGAGCAGUACAGCGUGGUGGUGGAGGAGGUGCCACUGCAGCCAGGCGAGAGCCUGCCCUACCACAGUGUCUACUACGAGGAUGAGUACGAUGACACAUACGAUGGCAACCAGGUGGGCGCCAAUGAUGCAGACUCUGAUGACGAGCUCAUCAGCCGCAGGCCAUUCACCAUCCCUCAGGUGCUGAGAACCAAAGUGCCUAGAGAAGGGCAGGAGGAGGAUGACGACGAUGAGGAAGACGAUGCUGACGAGGAGGCUCCCAAGGUACCUCCCUGGCAGCCCGACCAUUUUGUUCAGGACCCUGCAGUGCUGAGAGAGAAGGCAGAAGCCAGGCGCAUGGCCUUUCUCGCCAAGAAAGGGUACCGGCAUGACAGCUCAACAGCAGUGGCCGGCAGCCCCCGAGGCCAUGGGCAGAGCCGCGAGACAACCCAGGAACGCAGGAAGAAGGAAGCCAACAAGGCGACAAGAGCCAACCACAACCGGAGAACCAUGGCCGACCGCAAGAGGAGCAAAGGCAUGAUCCCAUCCUGAGACCUGGUGCAGGGCCAGUGGGGAGGCAGCGGCACCAGACUCACCAGGCCGUGCUCCCAUCGCCUGGGGCCUCCUCACUAGGGGCCCCAAGUUCAACUCAACCCCUCAACAGCCUCAGCUUUGCAGCCCCUGAGAAGGCCGCCUCUCAUCUACCAGCCAGCCAUGAGCGCCUUCCUGCAGAACACACAGUGCCUUAUGCCACAGCCGAAGAAUCCGUGGGGCCGGCAAGCAGGCACCUUCCCCCAGCUGCGCUAGCGGGAAAGAGAUGGGGAUGGAGUCCCAAGGCAAGCGCCCCAAACCUCGGGCCACAAGACACCACUUCCCCUUUACCCUGGACAGCAGGAAACCUGUAUAUUCAAAAACACAAAAAGUCCUGCUAAUAAAAUUUUUGACCCUUUCAAA